GCUGCGAAUCUGUCCUGAAGUUAAAGAGGAGACAGCAUUAGCCCUGGGUUCCUUUGGUGCUCUUACUUUUUCCCUCUGGGCCUCUCUUCUCCCUUGGCCUCUCCUGGCCUCCUUGAUUGAGGUAGUGGGAGGUAGUUAUAAUAGCUUACAGUAUUAUAUCUAUAAUACUAUUAUAAUAGCUAGUUAUAAUAGCUAGCUGUGUGACCUUGGAUUGGCUGUUUAUCCUUUCUGAGUCUCAGUGUUCUCAUCUGUAAGAUGGCGAUAAUGAUGAUUCUCAUUUGGCAGAGUUGUUGGAAUAGUAACCAUAGAAUGUGAGUUCCUGUCUUGCAUCAGGGGCUCAUUAAAAGUGGGUGUAUUUUCUUCUUCUUCUUUUUUUUUUUCCCCUGGAGAGCCCACUGUACCCUUUUCUUGGGUUCAAGACCUGGAGCCUUCUCGAUUUUCUCUUUUAUUGUUGAUUUGGCCCCAAAGGCCCCUCUGCACUUCCUCCAGGGCAUUUGUAUUUCAUCCUUAAAAGACUUUUGCUGAAGACCCAGCCUGGUGUCAUGGAGCUCACAGUCUCGCAGGACUACAGCACAGCCCUGGUGAAGCGUGGUGGCUCUUCUGUCACCUGCCCUGUGUGGGAGCAGCCGGAGGUGGGGGAUGGGGCUCUCGCUCUGAGGAGGGAGCAUUUGGUUUGACUCCUAGAGGCCAGAGCAGAGGUGGAAAGGAGCAAGGAGCAGGUGGAAGGGCACCCGGAGAGGUUUGUGAGGUGCUGGGAUGGCAGUGAGAGCUGCUGCGGGCGCUUGGGCUCCCACCUGCAGAGUCUCAGGUGUCACCUCGGCCUCCGUGGCCCCUCAGACUAGGACUGCCCUGCCUCCACAUCCCGAGCCUCAGGACUUCCGUGUGGGUGGCAGGUGCUUUCGGAAUGGAUGCCCUUCCGCCUAGUGUCUGCCCUCCUAGUACAGCAGGGGGCCGGCAUGCUUCAUGCUCCCUGUGAGGGUCGACUGGCGUAUGCACGUCCUUCAGCAGUGUCCUUGGGCCAAGUGUGGCACUGAGUCCUGCAGACACCCAGGGAGAGGGCAGGAGGCACCGGGUCAGAAAUCUGGGGCAGGUGAGGAGCAUGGGCAUCUGCGUCAGGAGAGACUUCCUCUCUGAAAUCCCCACCUGGGGCCAUCACGGCCUGCAUUGUGUGUGAAUACAUUUCUGAAUGUUAUAAAACAUCAGUGGGAAAGAAAAGCUUGAGGGUAGCUUUGCUAAAGCUUCUGUUUGGUUCCGUGACCAUUUACUGAGUUGUGACGGUACCAAGAACACAGGAGGAAUGAGGCUUCUUUCUUCAAGAACUUGGCCAGCGAGCAAUUCAACACAAGAUAGGUGACGAAUGAUGUGACCAAGGGAAGCACAGGGGCCAUGUGAGCCUGGGGCCUGGACCCUGGGAGCACCUGGGAAGCCCUCCUGGGGGAGAUGGCCCUUGAGCUGGUAUUGGUCAGGUGUCUUCUGCUUAUAAGUCGUGGACAGCUGUAUGAUUUCCUGUGGCUCCUGUAAGAAAGUCCCACAGACUUGGUUGCUUAAAAGUAGCACAAAUUUGUUCUUUUCCAGUUAGGCCGGUCAGAAGUCCAAAGUCGGCUCUCCCUGUGGUGGCUCCUGGGGCUCUGGGCUGGCAUGGUGUGGGCAGUUGUGGGCAUUGGAGGAGAGACAUCCUGGGCUCAAGUCUCCCGGGGAAGACUGAUGGCUCAGUGUGGGCCAUGUGUUCCUCCUUGAAGCAAUCACUGCAGUCUCUGGCUGGAAUCGGGGAGCAGCUCUCCCCAUACAUGGAAUUGGGUCAGGGUCCUCCACAAAACAAGGGAAGUUGAGCGACAAAAAUAGCCCACAGAGAACAAAAAGGAACAAACCAGCAUGUGUGCCUGCUGGAUUCACACAGGACCAGACUGAGUCUGGUCCUCAGGAAUACCUGGCCCACAUGCAGCAUCUGCGUGCACUGUGGGUGGAGGCGGGACGCUGGGCCAAGGAUGCAGCGUCUGGGUGCACUGUGGGUGGAGGCGGGACCCUGGGCCAAGGAUGCAGCGUCUGGGUGCACUGUGGGUGGAGGCGGGACCCUGGGCCAAGGCCCCUCUCAGGCUGCCUGGUCAUGUCCUCUCGGUUCCCACACAUGCCGGGAGCAUGCAGGGGGUGAACCAUUAGCACAACCCUUCUCAAACUUUUUGGUCUCAGAUCCCUUUACCCUUUAAAAGAUUAUUGAGGACCCCAAAGAACUUUUGUUUAUGUGAGUUAUAUCUACCAAUGUUUACUGCCAUAGAAGUUAAAACUGAGAAAUGUUAAAAAUAUUAAUUUAUUUAAAAAUAAGGCUGUGACAUGUUAACAUAAAAACAUUUUUUACAAAAACCAACUAUAUUAUCCAAAACAAAAAAAAAUUUAGAAGAGUGGGAUUCUUUUGCAUUCUUGCAAAUAUCUUUACAGUCUCCUUAAGAGAGGACAGCUGAAGGCUCCUGUUUGCUUCUGUACUCAGUCUGUUGCCUUGUGUUGCCUUGGUUGAAGUAUGUGAAGGAAAUCCAUCCCGAUCUAGUUAGGGAGGAGUCUCUUGGGUCAUUGUGGAUAUUCUUUGCUGCUGCAUUGAAACCCUACGAGCAGAAGUUUCUUAAGGAUUUGUUCUAAAGCAGAGUCUCCACCAUGUGAAUGAACUCUUCGUGCUCUGACAUUAAACUCCUUUGGUCUGUCUUGCACUUUGGGUGGAUGUUUUCUUCUUGCAGGAUUUUGUACCAUUACGCAUUGUUCAGAAAAUAUUGGUUCACGGAGUCAUGCAGACCUUCCAACUAUUGACACAUUUAAUGGUGUAACCUUAGAAGAUCACGUUAUAUCACUGCCCCUCUCAUCAGGAAAGUCUUGAAGAAGUGUGAAGCUAGUAGGCUCAUGGUAGAGGAUACAAAUGUUCUUAAUUCUCAUUUUUGCUUGGAAACUCCAUUUUUGUUGCAGUUGUUUUCCCGGAAGUGACAUGCUAACUUUGUUCACGUUUGAGAAGAUGUCUGCCAAGUACCCAUGUUUGUCUCUCAGUCAUUCUUCUUAGUGAAAAUGGUGUUGAAUAAUAAAAGCGGUGUGUUCAGCAUGCAGCCCAGUCACAGCCAGGCUUCCCCGGGGAUGACUGUUGCCUUUCAGUUUGCAGCAGAAAUGCUUGUUGUGUAUUUUCCAUUUCGUCUCACAAAAUUAAGAACGUGUGUACUCAAAGGUCAAGAAGUAAUAAGAUUAAUAGUUUUUCCGGCUUCACCAAGGAUGUUCUUACUUGAAGCUGCCUUGUUCUUUUCUGUGAGAGGUUGGGAGGACCUCACUCAACCCAACCAGCCUUGGGUUGAGUGAGGCCCCAGUGGCUUUCCCUGCUGCUGCCUCUGCCCCACCAUGCCACCAUGGUGAAAGAGAUAACACCUGGGUGUCAUGAAAAUAGUUUUGACCUUGUAGAGCCCCUGACAGGAUCCUGUUGAACCUUGGGUUUGGGGAAUGUACUUAGAGAGCUGCUGUCUUAGAAGGCCAAACCCACUUCUUUUUCUCCUUACUCGCCAUUUUAGUUUACGGAAUUCAACCUCUUCUUGAGGUUCAGAUCUUUGGAUUCUGUGUUGGCUAGAGAAGAUUUAGAUCCCGGUCUGGCUGGACAGGAUCAGAUAACACUCAAAACGGGCCAAGACCCACCAAGAAGCUGGUAACACCUGAAACCUGUCCCCAAAUGGCUUUAGCAACAAGAGACUUUGUUCAUGUAGCUGAAGUGUCGUGGGGUGACCAACUGAGGUCUCUAAUAAUGACAUGGGGACCCAGUGGCCCUCACUCCUACCUUUUCCUCUCUGCUUGUUUUUAUGUGUGUCCUAAGGUGGCCCCGGGCAGUUUCAGGCUGACCACCUCUUGGCCCAAGGGCUGUAUUCCCUCUCUCAUGCUCCCUGGGUCCCCUACAAGACAGUCUUAACGCUAGGACUGUAUUUCAGCAGCCACCCACCCCUGGUGUCCUUGUGUGGUAUCCAACUUACACAGCUGAAUAAAACAUCCCUUCAUGUCCCCAUCCGGAACCAGCCACAGAGGUAAUUCGCAUAGUUCAAAGUUGACAAGGAUACACAGGAAAAGUGAAUCAUCCCAUGUUGACCCCAGAGAGCGCGCCAGCCUUGGAAGGAAUCCACGGCAUUCCAGUGUGUCCUCAAGUGGCUGGACGGACCGGUAAUUAGGCAGGGCGUGCUGGAGGUACUGUCAGAGGUUGAAUGCCAUCUGCGAGUGUCUUUCUUUGAUGUCACCUACCGGCACUUCUUUGGGAGGACGUGGAAAACCACAGUGAAGCCGACGAAGAGACCGCCGUCCAGGAUCGUCUUUAAUGAGCCCUUGUAUUUUCACACAUCCCUAAACCACCCUCAUAUCGUGGCUGUGGUGGAAGUGGUCGCUGAGGGCAAGAAACGGGAUGGGAGCCUCCAGACAUUGUCCUGUGGGUUUGGAAUUCUUCGGAUCUUCAGCAACCAGCCGGACUCUCCUAUCUCUGCUUCCCAGGACAAAAGGUUGCGGCUGUACCAUGGCACCCCCAGAGCCCUCCUGCACCCGCUUCUCCAGGACCCCGCAGAGCAAAACAGACACAUGACCCUCAUUGAGAACUGCAGCCUGCAGUACACGCUGAAGCCACACCCGGCCCUGGAGCCUGCGUUCCACCUUCUUCCUGAGAACCUUCUGGUGUCUGGUCUGCAGCAGAUACCUGGCCUGCUUCCAGCUCAUGGAGAAUCCGGCGACGCUCUCCGAAAGCCUCGCCUCCAGAAGCCCAUCACGGGGCACUUGGAUGACUUAUUCUUCACCCUGUACCCCUCCCUGGAGAAGUUUGAGGAAGAGCUGCUGGAGCUCCACGUCCAGGACCACUUCCAGGAGGGAUGUGGCCCACUGGACGGUGGUGCCCUGGAGAUCCUGGAGCGGCGCCUGCGUGUGGGCGUGCACAAUGGUCUGGGCUUCGUGCAGAGGCCGCAGGUCGUUGUACUGGUGCCUGAGAUGGAUGUGGCCUUGACGCGCUCAGCUAGCUUCAGCAGGAAAGUGGUCUCCUCUUCCAAGACCAGCUCCGGGAGCCAAGCUCUGGUUUUGAGAAGCCGCCUCCGCCUCCCAGAGAUGGUCGGCCACCCUGCAUUUGCGGUCAUCUUCCAGCUGGAGUACGUGUUCAGCAGCCCUGCAGGAGUGGACGGCAAUGCAGCUUCGGUCACCUCUCUGUCCAACCUGGCAUGCAUGCACAUGGUCCGCUGGGCUGUUUGGAACCCCUUGCUGGAAGCUGAUUCUGGAAGGGUGACCCUGCCUCUGCAGGGUGGGAUCCAGCCCAACCCCUCGCACUGUCUGGUCUACAAGGUACCCUCAGCCAGCAUGAGCUCUGAAGAGGUGAAGCAGGUGGAGUCGGGUACACUCCGGUUCCAGUUCUCGCUGGGCUCAGAAGAACACCUGGAUGCACCCACGGAGCCUGUCAGUGGCCCCAAAGUGGAGCGGCGGCCUUCCAGGAAACCACCCACGUCCCCUUCGAGCCCGCCAGCGCCAGUACCUCGAGUUCUCGCUGCCCCGCAGAACUCACCUGUGGGACCAGGGUUGUCAAUUUCCCAGCUGGCGGCCUCCCCGCGGUCCCCGACUCAGCACUGCUUGGCCAGGCCUACUUCACAGCUACCCCAUGGCUCUCAGGCCUCCCCGGCCCAGGCACAGGAGUUCCCGUUGGAGGCCGGUAUCUCCCACCUGGAAGCCGACCUGAGCCAGACCUCCCUGGUCCUGGAAACAUCCAUUGCCGAACAGUUACAGGAGCUGCCGUUCACGCCUUUGCAUGCCCCUAUUGUUGUGGGAACCCAGACCAGGAGCUCUGCAGGGCAGCCCUCGAGAGCCUCCAUGGUGCUCCUGCAGUCCUCCGGCUUUCCCGAGAUUCUGGAUGCCAAUAAACAGCCAGCCGAGGCUGUCAGCGCUACAGAACCUGUGACGUUUAACCCUCAGAAGGAAGAAUCAGAUUGUCUACAAAGCAACGAGAUGGUGCUACAGUUUCUUGCCUUUAGCAGAGUGGCCCAGGACUGCCGAGGAACAUCAUGGCCAAAGACUGUGUAUUUCACCUUCCAGUUCUACCGCUUCCCACCCGCAACGACGCCACGACUGCAGCUGGUCCAGCUGGAUGAGGCCGGCCAGCCCAGCUCUGGCGCCCUGACCCACAUCCUCGUGCCUGUGAGCAGAGAUGGCACCUUUGAUGCUGGGUCUCCUGGCUUCCAGCUGAGGUACAUGGUGGGCCCUGGGUUCCUGAAGCCAGGUGAGCGGCGCUGCUUUGCCCGCUACCUGGCCGUGCAGACCCUGCAGAUUGACGUCUGGGACGGAGACUCCCUGCUGCUCAUCGGAUCUGCUGCCGUCCAGAUGAAGCAUCUCCUCCGCCAAGGCCGGCCGGCUGUGCAGGCCUCCCACGAGCUUGAGGUCGUGGCAACUGAAUACGAGCAGGACAACAUGGUGGUGAGUGGAGACAUGCUGGGGUUUGGCCGCGUCAAGCCCAUCGGCGUCCACUCGGUGGUGAAGGGCCGGCUGCACCUGACUUUGGCCAACGUGGGUCACCCGUGUGAACAGAAAGUGAGAGGUUGUAGCACAUUGCCACCGUCCAGAUCUCGGGUCAUCUCAAACGAUGGAGCCAGCCGCUUCUCUGGAGGCAGCCUCCUCACGACUGGAAGCUCAAGGCGAAAACACGUGGUGCAAGCACAGAAGCUGGCGGACGUGGACAGUGAGCUGGCUGCCAUGCUACUGACCCAUGCCCGGCAGGGCAAGGGGCCCCAGGACGUCAGCCGCGAGUCGGAUGCCACCCGCAGGCGUAAGCUGGAGCGGAUGAGGUCUGUGCGCCUGCAGGAGGCCGGGGGAGACUUGGGCCGGCGCGGGACGAGCGUGUUGGCGCAGCAGAGCGUCCGCACACAGCACUUGCGGGACCUACAGGUCAUCGCCGCCUACCGGGAACGCACGAAGGCCGAGAGCAUCGCCAGCCUGCUGAGCCUGGCCAUCACCACGGAGCACACGCUCCACGCCACGCUGGGGGUCGCCGAGUUCUUUGAGUUUGUGCUUAAGAACCCCCACAACACACAGCACACGGUGACUGUGGAGAUCGACAACCCCGAGCUCAGCGUCAUCGUGGACAGUCAGGAGUGGAGGGACUUCAAGGGUGCUGCUGGCCUGCACACACCGGUGGAGGAGGACAUGUUCCACCUGCGUGGCAGCCUGGCCCCCCAGCUCUACCUGCGCCCCCACGAGACCGCCCACGUCCCCUUCAAGUUCCAGAGCUUCUCUGCAGGGCAGCUGGCCAUGGUGCAGGCCUCUCCUGGGUUGAGCAACGAGAAGGGCAUGGACGCCGUGUCACCUUGGAAGUCCAGCGCAGUGCCCACUAAACACGCCAAGGUCUUGUUCCGAGCGAGUGGUGGCAAGCCCAUCGCCGUGCUCUGCCUGACUGUGGAGCUGCAGCCCCACGUGGUGGACCAGGUCUUCCGCUUCUAUCACCCGGAGCUCUCCUUCCUGAAGAAGGCCAUCCGCCUGCCGCCCUGGCACACAUUUCCAGGUGCUCCGGUGGGAAUGCUUGGUGAGGACCCCCCAGUCCAUGUUCGCUGCAGCGACCCGAACGUCAUCUGUGAGACCCAGAAUGUGGGCCCCGGGGAACCACGGGACAUAUUUCUGAAGGUGGCCAGUGGUCCAAGCCCGGAGAUCAAAGACUUCUUUGUCAUCAUUUACUCGGAUCGCUGGCUGGCGACACCCACACAGACGUGGCAGGUCUACCUCCACUCCCUGCAGCGCGUGGAUGUCUCCUGCGUCGCAGGCCAGCUGACCCGCCUGUCCCUUGUCCUUCGGGGGACACAGACAGUGAGGAAAGUGAGAGCUUUCACCUCUCAUCCCCAGGAGCUGAAGACAGACCCCAAAGGUGUCUUCGUGCUGCCGCCUCGUGGGGUGCAGGACCUGCAUGUUGGCGUGAGGCCCCUUAGGGCCGGCAGCCGCUUUGUCCAUCUCAACCUGGUGGACGUGGAUUGCCACCAGCUGGUGGCCUCCUGGCUCGUGUGCCUCUGCUGCCGCCAGCCGCUCAUCUCCAAGGCCUUUGAGAUCAUGUUGGCUGCGGGCGAAGGGAAGGGUGUCAACAAGAGGAUCACCUACACCAACCCCUACCCCUCCCGGAGGACAUUCCACCUGCACAGCGACCACCCGGAGCUGCUGCGGUUCAGAGAGGACUCCUUCCAGGUCGGGGGUGGAGAGACCUACACCAUCGGCUUGCAGUUUGCGCCUAGUCAGAGAGUGGGUGAGGAGGAGAUCCUGAUCUACAUCAAUGACCAUGAGGACAAAAACGAAGAGGCAUUUUGCGUGAAGGUCAUCUACCAGUGAGGGCUUGAGGGUGACGUCCUUCCUGCGGCACCCAGCUGGGGCCUGUCUGUGCCCCUCCUGCCCUGCAGGCUGUCCUCCCCGCCUCUCUGCAGCCUUUCACUUCAGUGCCCACCUGGCUGACCUGUGCACUUGGCUGAGGAAGCAGAGACCGAGCGCUGGUCAUUUUGUAGUACCUGCAUCCAGCUUAGCUGCUGCUGACACCCAGCAGGCCUGGGUUCCGUGAGCGCGAACUCCGUGGUGGUGGGUCUGGCUCUGGUGCUGCCAUCUACGCAUGUGGGACCCUCGUUAUCGCUGUUGCUCAAAAUGUAUUUUAUGAAUCAUCCUAAAUGAGAAAAUUAUGUUUUUCUUACUGGAUUUUGUACAAACAUAAUCUAUUAUUUGCUAUGCAAUAUUUUAUGCUGGUAUUAUAUCUGUUUUUUAAAUUGUUGAACAAAAUACUAAACUUUUACACGUC